UGCUCUCUGCUUUUGUUUCUUUGUUUUUGUUUUGUUUUGGGACAGAGAUAGGAAGGUUGAAUGGGGCCCCAGAGAUCUAAGAGUAAAGGAGGAGGGGAGAGAAAUUUGUAGUGAUGAGUGUUUUCUGCUGUAAGAGUCCUGAGAGAAUGUAAGAGUUUGAUUCUGGCAGAAGCAAACUGGCAAUGUGGGUCAAGAAUUAACCAACAGGAAUGCCAGGAUAACAUCUCCUGAGACAUGUCUCUAAAUUACAUCAAAAACUUCUAUGAAGGAUGUGUUAAACCUCCAACUGUGAUUGGUCAAUUCCACACCCUUUUCUUUGGAUCGAUCCGAAUAUUCUUCCUCGGGGUGCUAGGCUUUGCAGUUUAUGGGAAUGAGGCCUUGCACUUCAUUUGCGAUCCAGACAAAAGAGAAGUAAACCUCUUCUGUUACAAUCAGUUCAGGCCAAUCACUCCACAAGUAAGUUUUUCUGCAUUACAACUAGUUAUUGUCCUGGUUCCUGGAGCUCUUUUCCACCUUUAUGCUGCAUGUAAAAGCAUCAAUCAAGAAUGCAUUCUUCAAAAGCCUAUCUACACUAUAAUUUAUAUACUCUCUGUUUUAUUAAGAAUUAGUCUAGCGGCAAUAGCAUUCUGGCUUCAGAUUUACCUCUUUGGUUUCCAAGUAAAAUCUCUUUACCUGUGUGAUGCUAGAUCUCUUGGGGAAAACAUGAUUAUAAGAUGCAUGGUUCCAGAACACUUUGAAAAAACCAUUUUUCUCAUUGCAAUAAAUACAUUUACAACAAUUACAAUUUUAUUAUUUGUUGCUGAGAUUUUUGAGAUCAUAUUUAGAAGAUUAUACUUUCCAUUCAGACAAUGACCAAAUAAUUACCUAUUGUCAUGCUGCAGUUAUUUAUCAUUUUUAUUUAGUUUUAUCUUACUCAGUGAGUACAAUUUCAAAACAAACUUACUUCAAUGUGUCUGAAAUUUUUGUCUACUAUAAAAUAUAGUGCCUGGUUGUAAGGUAAGGAUUCUUGAAGAAAUAUUUCAUUUUAAUUUUGAUCACUUUUAUUAGAAAAUAUACACAGAACUACUGUUAAUUUAUUUUUAAACAGUGCUUUUACAGAGUUCUCUCACAUACAUGUUAAUUGAUCAGUUUUUCUGUGGCCAGAGAAACUUUUAUUGUCUUUUUUUACGAAGUGGAAAAUUGAUGCUCAUGAGGGUUAAUUUAGGUGGUCAAAGUCAUAAUCCAGAUAUUUAUAUUUCCCUUUCUGUGGAACUAUACAGUUUUAAAUUUGAGGGUGUAAUUAUUUUGC